ACAGCUUACCAUGGGGUUCCCUCCAGAGUGCAGUUCUGUUUCUCCUCUCUUUCUCUCUCUCCAUACCGUACCAUGUGACUCCCUCUACAGUGCAAUUCUGGUUUUCCUUUUUUAUAUUAGUCACUUUUAUUGAGGUAUACUUAACAGAAAAUAAAAUUCAGCACCUUUCAGUGUACAAAUCAAUGAGUUUUGAAAAAUGUAUACAUUGAUUACCACAAUCCAAAUCAUGGUUUGGAAUAUUUUUAUCACCCCCCAGAAGAUUCUUUGUAGCCCUUUGCAGUGAGUCCCCUCCCUCCAUCCCUUCCUCCACAACCCCUGGCAACUACUAGUCUGCUUUCUAUUGCAAUAAUUUUGCCUUUUCUCAAAUUUCAUAUAAAUGGAAUCAUAAAUUAUAUACUCCCUUUUGUCUGGCUUUUCUUUAGUAUAAUGCUUUUGAAACUCAUGCACAUGUGUGUAUAAGUGGUUAAUUAUUUUAUCCUAAGUAGUGCCGCUUUGUGGGUAUAUACUGCAAUUUAUUAUCCUUUAUCAGUUGGUCAACAUACGGAAUUUUUUCCCAGUUGGUGCUUUUCUGAGUAAAGCUGCUAUGAACUUUCACAUACAAGUCUUUGUGUCAACAUAUGUUUUCAUUUCUCUUGUAUAAGUACCUAGGAGUGAGCUUGCCAGGUCUUUGGUAAGUUUAUCUGUCUGUAACUUUAUGAGAAACUGCCAAAUGUUUUCAAACUGGCUCCACAGUUUUUCAUUUUCAUGAACAGUGUCUGUGAGUUCUCAUUACUCUUUGGUUACCAUUAUUUGGAAAAUUUUGCUGUUUUUAACAGUUCUAGUUGGGUUUUAAUUUGCAUUUUCCUGAUGACUAACAACAUUGAACCUCUUUUUAUGUGCUUUUUAGCGAUUCAUAAAUCUUCUUUAAGUGACCAGUCAAAUCUUUAGCUCAUUUUUGUUUCGUUUAGUUUUUAGUAUUUUUGUUUGUUUAGUUGAAGAAGUUCAGACCUUUAUUAGAUAUAUGUUUUACAGACUUUUUCUUGCCAUCUCUUGCUUCUCUUUUUAAAGAGAAAAUGUUUUCAGUUUUUGAUUUUUUGCAUAUAUUUUAAGAAACCUUUUUUAUAUUGAAAUAAUUAUAGAUUUAUGGGAAUUAGCAAAAAUUGUGUCCUCACUUUAGCUUACCCCAAAGGUUACAUGUUUUAUAACUAUAAUACACUAUCAACACCAGUAAAUAGACACUGGUACAAUGUGUGUGAAUAGCUCUGUGCCAUUUUAUCACAUGUGGAGAUUGAUGUAACCACCACAGUUACAAUUCAGAACUGCUCUAUCACCACAAAGAUCUCUUUGGUGCUACUCAUUCAUAGUCACACCCAUGCUGUCUCUCACAUUGUUCCUGAUCUCUGCUGACUACUAAUCUGCUAGCUCUAUAAUUUUGUCAUUUUGAGACUGUUAUAUAAGUGGAAUCAUACAGUAUUUGACGUGUUGAGACUGGCUUUUUCACUCAGCGUAAUGCUCUUGAGAUCCAAGUUGUAGUGUAUCCGUAGUUCAUUCCUUUUAUAGCUACGUAGUAUUUCACUGUAUGAAUAUCAUUGUUUAGCCAUUCACCUAUUAAAGGACAUUUUGGUUGUUUCCAUUUUGGGGCUAUUAUAAAGUUGAUGUGAACAUUCAUGUUCAGAUUUUUUGUGAACAUAAGUUUUUCUGGGAUAAGUGCCAUGGAGUGUGAUUGUUGGAUUGUAUGGUAAGUUAUGUUUUAUUCUUUAAGAAAGUGCCAAACUAUUUCCCAGAGUUGCUGUACCAUUUUGCAUUUCCACCAGCAAUGUAUGAGGGAUCCAGUUAUUCCCUAUCCUUUCUGGUACUAGGCAUUGUUGCUAUUUUAUGUAUUAGUCGUUGAACAGGUGUAUAGCAAUAUCUCAUAGUGAUCCUAAUUUGCAUUUCCCUAAUGGCUACUGAUAAUCAAAUAUCUUUUCAUGUGUUCACAUGCCAUCUGUGUAUCCUUAGUAAAAUGUCUGUUCAUGGCUUUUGUCCAUUUUUUAAUUGGAAGUUUGUGUGUUUUACCAUUGACUUUUGAGAAUUUAGAUAGUCUAGAUAUGAGUUUCUUUGUCAGAUGUGUGGUUUGCACAUUUUUAUACCAGUCUGUAACUUGUCUUUUCAUCCUCUUCAUGGGGUGUUUUGUAGAGCAUAAGUUUUUAAUUUUGAUGAAGUCCAGUUUAUCAGUUUUGUAAAAAUGUUGUCCUAUCUAAGAACUCUUCACUAAGUCUUUGGACCAAAGGUUUUCUCCUAUUUUUAAAAAUUGUGUAAUAUAUUUUACAUUUUAAUUAUGGUACAUUUUGAGUAAAUUUUUGUAUAGGGCAUGAAGUGUAAGUUGAGAUCUUUUUUUGUUUGUUUUUGCCUAUGGAUAUCCAUUUGCUCCAUGCAACACCAUUACCCUUCAUUGAAUAGCUUUUUCACCUGUGUCAAAAAUCAGUUGGCUGUACUUGUAUGAGACUAUUAUAUUCCCACAUUAUAUUUCUUUUUCAAUAUUGUUUUAACUAUUCUAGUUACUUCACCUUUGCAUAUACAUAUUGUAAUAAUAUCAUUAUGUUAAAAUCUUACUGGGUGUUUGAUAGGAAUUAAAGCUAUAAAUUAUCAAUUUUGUGACAGUUAACAUCUUUACUGUUUUGAGUCUUGAGGCUUAUAAUCCAUAAACACAAUAUAUUUCUCCAUUUACUUAGAUCUUGAUUUCUUGCUUCAGUGUUUUGUGAUUUUCAGUAUAAAAGUCCUGUACAUGUUAUAUUUAUACCUCAGUAUUUCAUUUGGUUGAGUAAUUGUUAAUGGCAUUGUGUUUUAAAUUUCUGUUUGCUUACAAAGGUUGCUAGUUUAUAGAAAUGUAAUUGAUUUUUGUAUGUUUGUUCUUUUAUGCUGAGAUCUUGCUGAACUUUCUAGGGAGGCUUUUUGUAGAUUCCUUGGCAUUUUUUAACAUAAGCUAUCAUGUCAUAUAUGUAUAGGGUCAGUUUACUACUUUCCUUUCUAAUCUGUAUGCUUUUUAUUUCCUUUUCUUGUUGUAUUACACUGGAUAGGACUUCUAGUACUGUGUAGAAUAAGAGUGGUAAGAGUAGUCAUCCUUGCCUUGUUCCCAACCUUAAGGGGAAAACAUCUAGUCUUUCACCAAAUGAUCUUUUGUAGAUAUUCUUCAUCAAAUGGUGGAACUUCUUCUGUAUUCCUAGUUUUCUGAGAAUAUUGAUUAUGAAUGGAUAUUGAAUCUUGUCAAAUACUUUUUAUGUAUAUACUGCUGUGAUUACAUGGUUUUUCUUCAUUACUCCAUUAAUGUAAUAGACUUUGUUGACUAGUUUUCAAAUAUUGAACCAGCCUUAUAUACUUGGAAUAAACCUUACUUGGUAAUGUCAUAGAAUUCUUUUUAUUUAUUGUUUGAUUCUAUUUGCUAAUAUUUUGUUAAGUAGUUUUGCAUUUAUGAGAGAAAUUGGUCUGUAGUUUUGUACUGCCUUUGUCUGGUUUUCAUAUCAGCAUAAGUCUGGCCUCAUAAAAUUAGUUGGAAAGUGUUCCUUCCAAUUUUCUGGAAGAGGUUGUAUAGAAGUGGUGUUUAUUCUUCAUUAAAUGUUUGAUAGAGUUAUCUAGUGAAACCAUCUGGGCCUAGAGACUUCUUUUUGGGAAGUUUUACAAAUCAAUUUAUUUAAGUCAUAUAUAUGGAUAUUCAAAUUAUUUCUAUUAGGUGAAUUGUGGUAUUUUUGCUUUUCUAACAAUGAGUCCAUUUUAUCUCAGUUGUCACAUUCAUAUGUGUAAAGAUGUUCAGACCAUUCCAUUAUUAUCAUUUUGAUGUCUUCAGGAUCUGUAUUUAUAGACCUGUUUUAUUCUUUAUAUUGGUCAUUUCUGUCUUCUUGCUCUUUUAUUUUUUUGUUCACUCUUCCUACAGGUUUUACAAGGUUACUGCUCUUUUCAGCCAACCAGCUUUUUCUCUCAUUGAUCUUUCUCUUUUGUUUUUUUGGUUUUAAUUUAGUUGAUUUCUACUCUUAACUUUUUACUUUUGCUUCUGUUAGGAUUAUUGUGCUCUUUGUCUAGCUUUUUAAUGUGAGAUCAUGCACUAUUAAUUUGAGACUUUUUCUCUUUUCUAACGUACACAUUUAGUGCCAUAAAAAAUUCAGCACUGCUUUAGCUGCAACAUGCAAAUUGCAUAUCGGGUUACUAAGACGUGUCUCUUAUUUAUGUCUAGAAGACAUAUUUCUUCUUUGAUUGAACACUCAUUCAUAUAGUAUGAGACUGUAUGAAGAAAUGCAAUUAAAACUUAACAACUGUUUAAUUAAUAUCCACUUUUUGAUAGACACCAGUGCAGUUCUCAAGUUAUUCAAUAGCACAGCCUUAAUUUUCAUAGGGUGAUUUGAAGAGUUUCUGAGGUUAAGAAAACCUUUCUGUUAAAAAAAAUUGUAAUUUUUUUGAAGCUGGGUGAAGGAUACAUGAGGGGAGGGGUUCACUGAACUCUCUUUUUUACUUUUUCAAAGAAAAUUUUCAAAUUCAAAGGAAAAGAUAAGUGUUGCUUGAGAAAAACUCUAAGGAUGUCUAGGAAUAAGCUAAAUAAGGAAAUAUAAACACUCCAAGCAGAGAAAAGAACAAGCACAAAGACCCCUAGUAGAAGAAAAGAUAGUGAGUACAGAGACCUGAAAAAGAACCAGUACACCUGGAACAAAGAAAGCAAGAAGGAAUAUGGUACAAGAUGUGGAAGUGGACCAAGUGAAUAUAUAUUAUUGAGGCCAUAUUCUGGGUUUAAAGCAAUAAGUAGUCAUUGAGGGCUUUAAAUAAAAUAGUAAUCAACCAUAUCUGCUAAGAAAUGUAAUUUUUUGGCACUAAAAGAAAUUACAGGUGCAUUAAUUUUUACUCAGCAACAUAUACAGUACUCAGCAACAAUACCUGCAUAAACACAAAAUGAUAUAUACACAAGGUUAUUCAUUGCAGCAUUGUUUGUAAGAGCAAUAGAAUAUCAACAACCCAAAUGUACAUCAUUGACUAAUUGGCUAAAAGUGUGUUACUUCUACACACAAAUGAAGACUAUGCAACUAUAAAAUGGACAAGAGCCUGUAUACAAAUAAGGAGUGAUACUCAGUAAAUAUUAAGUCAAAAGAAGCAGUAGAAUGGUGUGCAUAGGAAGCCAUCUUUGAGUAAGGAAAGAGAGAAGAAUAUACGUAACUGUUGAUAUUUGCAAAAAUGAAACACUGGGAGAAAAAUCAGAAAGUAAUAAAAUUUAGCAGGUGGGGGGGGUGAGUGAUUAGAGCAGGAAUGGAAGUGAGACUUUUAAUAUACCUUUUUAUACAAUUUGGAUUUUUGAACUACAUACGUUUUGCAUAUUGAAAGAUUACACUAAAUUUAAAAGGUAGUUCUUAAAUGUGAAAGUUUUAGAGACUGAUGGUUCCAGAUAAGAUUGAUUACAGAUACUUCUUCCUGUUCCUCCCUUUAAGUACAGCUAAAACCACUAGACAUUAUAUACAAAACACAUAAGAAGACUUUGAACAGUGAGAGAAGGACACAGACAAGCUAGGGACAUUGGAACCCAAGAAAUGACACCUCUUUCUCAGUUUUAUUUUUGCCUAAUGUAUCAGCCUGAAACACCAAUUGGUACAGACAAAAAAAAAAAAAAAAAAAAAGUCCCAAGUAAAGCCUGCUUCCUCUAGACAAAAGAACAGGAAAGCAACCACCCAGAAAGACAGAAAAUUUUAGACAACUGCCCUACCCUAGCUAAACACUAUGGAAAAAAACUGCAGCUCUCUUCCAUCACCAAAAACUGACUUCCACCCUGGUUCUAGAGUAUCAGAGUACUCCUCUAGCUCUCUAAUGGGGUGAUUUCAGAUGAGGCCUAGUGGUAAGCCAGGACUCUUCCUACCAACUGACAGUAAAAAGUUGCCUGGAUAGGCCAGGCGCUGUGGCUCACGACUGUAAUCCCAGCACUUUGGGAGGCCGAGGUAGGUGGAUCACGAGGUCAGGAGUUCAAGACCAGCCUGGCCAACAUGGUGAAACCCCAUCUCUACUAAAAAUACAAAAAUUAGCCAGGCGUGGUGGUGGGUGCCUGUAAUUCCAGCUACUUGGGAGGCUGAGGCAGGAGAAUCACUUGAACCCCGGAGACGGAGGUUGCAGUGAGCCAAGAUCACUCCACUGCACUCCAGCCUGGGCAACAAGAGCAAGACUCUGUCUCAAAAAAAAAAAAAAAGAAAAGAAAAAUACAUCAGGCUAACACUAAUCAAAAUUGAAAUAACUAUUAAUUUCAGACAAAGCAGACUUCACAACAUGGAAGAUCAUCAAGGAUGGAAGAAUAUUACAUAGUAAUAAAUGGCUCAAUUCUCUAAGAAAACAUAACAGCCCUAGACAUUUAUGCAGUUAAAAACAGCUUCAAAUUAUAUGAGGUAAAAAACUGAUAGAACUAAAAAGAGAAAUACACAAAUCUACAAUUAAAAUAGGGAGAUUUAAACACCGCUCUGUCAGUAUUGGUAGAUCAAGCAGGCAGAAAAUUGCUGAGGAUAUAAAUGACCUGAACAGCAGUGUCAGCCAACUUGGAUCUACUGACAUUUUUAGACUACAGCAAUAGAAAAAUAUACAUUCUUCUCAAGUGCAUGUAAAACAUUCAUCCAAAGAGACAUUCUAGGCCAUAAAGCACACUUUAACAAAUGAAAAAGUACAGAAAUCAUAAAAAGUGUGCUUUCAAACCAUACCAGAAAUCAAAUACAGAAAGAUAGCAGGAGCAUUUCCAAAUAUUUGGAAAUAACCAACACACUUGUCAACACAUGAGUCAAAGAAAAAUUCUCAGUAUAAUUUUUUGAAAACGAAAGUACAAGAAAUUUGUGAAAUGCAGCUAAAGCAAUAAUCAGAGGUUAAUUUAAGUGUUAAGUGCACAUAAAAGAAAAAGGCAGGGCACAGAGGCUAACACCUAUAAUCCCAACACUUUGAAAGGCCAAGGUGGACGGAUCACUUGAACCCAGGAGCUCAAGACCAACCUGGGCAACAUAGGGAGAUUCUGUCUCUACAAAAAAAUAUAAAAAUGAGCCAGGCAUCAUGGUGGCAUGUGCCAGUAGUUCCAGCUACGUGAAAAUGAAUAACAGAAGGAAGACUAGAAAUGUUACAAAUAUGUGAAAAAUUAACAAACUCUUUAACUACCAAGGGGUCAAAAAAUCAUAAGACAAAUUAGAAAAUACCUUGAGAGAGAUGAAAAUACAACAUAGCGUACCUUCUGGAUGCAGUAAAACCAACAAUAAGAUGGAAAUGUAUAGCUAUAAACGCAUACAUUAAGGAAGAAGAAAGAUCUCAAAUAAUAACCUAACUUCACGUCUUAAGAAACUAAAGAAAGAGCAAACUAAACCUAAACCUAGCAAAAGGAAACAAUAGUAGAGAUUAGAAGAGAGAUAAUGAAAGAAUAGAAAAACAAUAGAGAAAAUCAAUGAAACCAAAGUUCUUUUUUAAAAAACCAACAAAAUUGAUAAACUUUUAACUAGAUCAGUUCAGAAAAAAAGGGAAGACUCAAAUUACUAAACUCAGAAAUGAAAAUGGGGACAGUAUUAGCAAUUCUACAGAAAUAAAACUGAUUAUAAAGGAAUGCUGUGAACAACAAAUUAACCUAAAUGAAAGAGACAAAUUACUUGAAGUACAUAAUCUACCAAAACUGAAUCAUGAAGAGAUAGAAAGCUCAAAUAGACCUGUAAGUAGUGUCUAGUACCAUUCACCAAGUAAAGGAACCAAGAUUCCUUGGGAAAAUGGUUGAUUCUAAGGGCUAGGCGAGAAAUGUACAAGAUGAGUGUGGGGCAUCUUGUAGAACCAGAAAGUAAGGAAAUUGCUCAAAAAACAAAACUAUGGGAGUGUCUCAGUCCAGUUUGUGUUGCUAGAACAGAAUACCUGAGACUGGGUAAUUUAUAAAGAAAAGUUUGUUUCGCUCACAAUUCUGGUGGCUGGAAAAUCCAGGAUUGGGCAGCUGCAUCUAAUGAGGGCAUCAUACUGCUUCAACUUAUGGUGGGAAGUGGAAGGGGAGGGGCCAUGUGCAAAGAGAUCACAUGGCAAAAGAGGAAGCAAGAGAGAAACCAGGCUCUUUAACAACCCGUUCUCACAAGAAAUAAUCUAUUCCUAUGAGAGUGAGAACUCAACCCUUUGGGAGGGCAUUAAUCUGUUCAUGAGGGAUCUACUCCCAUGACCCAAACAUCUCCCACUAAGCCCCACCUCCCAACACUGCUACAUUGGGGAUCAAAUUUCACCUUGAGUUUUUGCAGGGAUGAACCACACCCAAACCAUACCAUUCUGCCCCUAGCUCCCCAAAACUCAUGUCCUUCUCAUAUACAAAAUAUAAUAUUCCAUCCCACUAGUCCCAAAAGCCUUAAGUUUUUCUAGCACCACCUUAAAAGUCCAAAGUCCAGCUACAAGCCUGUAAAAUCAAAAAUAAGUUAUUGGGCAGGCAUGGUGGCUCACACCUAUAAUCCCAGCACUUUGGGAGGCCAAGGUGGGUGGAUCACCUGAGGUCAGGAGUUCAAGACCAACAUAGUGAAACCCCGUCUCUACUAAAAAUACAAAAAUUAGCCAGAUGUGGCAUGCGCCUAUAGUCUCAGCUACGCGGGAGGCUGAGGCAGGAGAAGCGCUUGAAUCCGGGAGGUGGAGAUUGCAGUGAGCUGAGAUCAGACCAUUGCACUCCAGCCUGGGCAACAGAGCAAGACUUGGUCUCAAAAAAAAAAAAAAAAAAGUUUUUUACUUCCAAGAUACAAUGGUGGAAUAGGCAUAAGGUCUGAAACCCAGCAGGGCAGACAUUAAAUUUGAAAGCUCCAGAAUAGUCUCCUUUGACUCCAUGUCCCACAUCCUCAGCACACUGGUGUGAGGAGUAGCCUUCCAAGCCCUUGGAUAGCUCCACUCUCAUGGCUUCUCUCUGCCCAGCUUACAUUGCUGCUCUCACAGGCUGAAGGCAAAUGCCUGCAGCUUUUCAAGACUGAGAUUGCAUGCUACUGGUGGCUCUACAAUUUUGGGGUCCUAGCAGUGGCCCUAAUCCUGAAGCUCCACUAGGCAUUGCCUUAGUGGAGACUCUGCAGUAGACCUAACCCAAAUUUUUGCUUGGCCUUGCCCUAGCAGAGGGUCUCUGCAGUGGCUCUGCCCCUGCAACAAGUCUCUGCCUGGGCCUAUAGGGUUUUUCAUACAUACGUUGAAAUCUCAGUGGAGUAACACACACCUCCAUGGCUCUAGCAUUCUGCAAGCCUGCAAAAUUAACACUACACGGACCCCAAGGCUUACUGCUCAUGCCCUCUAGACAUAAGCCAGGGGAUGUAAGGCUUAUGCAGCACAAGCCUUACUGGAGCCACUUGACCCCAUGGCUGUUUCAGCUGAAGCAGCUAGGAUGCAGGAAGCUGUGUCUCAAGGUGUCCCAAGUGCAGCAGCCUGGCCCUUUCCCCUGAAACUAUUCUGCCUUCUUAGGCUUCUGGGCCUGGAAUGGGAGAAGCAACUUGAAGAUAUUCAAAAUGACUUCAGGGUCUUUUUCCCAUUGUUUUGACCUUUUGCUUAUUCUAAUCUCUUUAGCAAGCAGUUGCUCAGCCACAUCAAUGGAUAUCUUUUCUAAAAAUUCUCCUUCAUUCUCUUCCACACGGCCAGGCUGCAAAUUUUCCAAAUCCUUCUACUUUGCUUCCUUUUAAAUUAUAAAUUCCAUCUUUAGAUUAUCCCUUUGCUAGUAUAACUCCAGCAUAAGCUGUUAAAAGUAACCAUGCCACUUCUUGAGCACUUUGCUGCCUAGAAGGUUCUUCCACCAGUUAUACUAGUUCACCACUCUUAAGUUCUGCCUUCCAUAAAGCCCUGAGGCAUGGAGACAAUACAGCCACCUUCUUUGCUACUGUGUAAAAAGGAUGGCCUUUUUUCCAGUUCCUAAUAAUGCUUCCUCAUUUCCAUCUGAGAUCUUAGCAGAAUGGUCUCUACUGUCAUAUUUCUAGCAGCAUUUUGUUCACAACCAUUUAACCAAUUUGUAAGAAGUCUGAAAGUUUCCUUUGUUUUCCUGUCUUCAUCUGAGCCUCAGUAGAAUCACCCUUAACGCUCCAUUCAUGGCAAUACUGGCCUGCCCCUCCAAAUUUUUCCAGCCACUACCCAUUACCCAGUUCCAAAGCUACUUCCGCAUUUUCAGGUGUUUGUAAAGCAACAACCCACUCCUUGGUACCAAUUUUCUCUCUUAGUCUGUUUUGUGUUGCCGUAACAUAACAAGUGAGACUAGGUGAUUUUUAAAGAAAAAACAUUUAUUUAGCUCACAAUUCUGGUGGCUGGGAAGUCCCAAAUUGGACAGCUUCAUCGGGUGAGGACGUCAUGCUGCUUCAACUCAUGGCAGAAAGUGGAAGGGGAGCAAGCAUGUGCAAAGAAAUUGCAUGGAAGCAAGAGUGUGAAACUGAGGAAUCUCUAAAUAACUCACUGUCACAGGAACUAGUACAUUCCUGUGAGAGCAAGAACUCACGCCCAUUGAAUGGUGUAUUAGUCCAUUCUUAUGCUGCUAUGAAGAAAUACCUGAGACUGGGUAAUAUAUAAAGGAAAGAAGUUUAAUUGACUCACAGUUUCACAUAGUUGGGGAGGCCUUAGGAAACUUGCAAUUAUAGUGGAAGGCACCUCUUCACAGGGCAGCAGGAGAGAGAAUGAGUGCCCAGUGAAGGGGGAAGCCCAUUAUAAAACCAUCAGCUCACGUGAGAACUAACUCACUAUCACGAGAAUAGGAUGGGGGAAACCGUCCCUAUGAUUCAGUUUUCUCCACCUGGUCCGUCCCAUGACGUGGGGAUUAUGGGAACUACAAUUCAAGAUGAGAUUUGGGUGGGGACACAGCCAAACCAUGUCAGAGGGCAUUAAUCUUUUCAUGAGGGAUCCAGCCCCGUGACCGAACACCUCCCACUAUGCCCCACCUCUCAACACUGCAUUAAGGAUCAAAUUUUAACAUGUAUUUUGAUGGGGACAAACCAUACCCAAACCAUAGCAGGGGAUACGUCAAAGAACAGGGGAGCCAACUGAAAGAUCUCCCAGUAGCCAAAAUUGCAACAGUUUGAGUAAUAAAAUAAACAACAUAGUAUUGGUUCAUAACCCAAAGUAUGAAAAACUCGUGAGUCCAUAUUGAUAUAAAUAAUUGAAUAAAUAAGAGAGAAUAGAAAAUCUCCCAAAUAGAAAAAUUCCUAAUAAUUUAUGUAGUUACUCCUCUUCAAGGAAGUGGAGCAUAAUUCUCCUCUGCUGUAGUGGACUGUGCCUGGUGACAGUCUUCUAAAAAGUAUAGUAUGCAUACUGGAGAAAAGGAAUAACUAUAAUGGAAAAUCCUGGCAUCCAUUACCUCCACCAGGUGAUCAAAGUUAUCGUCAGUGAUAAGUCUGUUGAUGGCAUAUUCCCUUGAUGAGAUGUGAUGAGAAUGGUAGACACUUUACCUCUGUGGUCUUUCUCUGAGGAAUACAUAACCCCACUUUAGUUAUGAGGAAAACAUCAGAUAAACCAAAACUGAAGAACAUUCUACAAUGUCCUUUAAACUGUCAAGGUGACCCAAAAUACCACAAAACACUUAUAGUUUACAGGAGCCUACAGAGACAGGAUGACUGAAUGUAAUGUGGGAUCUUGGAUGAAGCUAUAGAACAGGAAAAAGACAUUAGGUAAAAAGGAGCUCUGAAUAAAGUGUGGACUUUAUUUCAUAAUGUAUCAGUAUUAUUAGUUAUGAAAAAACUGCCAUCGGAAUUUCUGAUGUUAUAUGAGAAAACUGGUAGUUUCAGUUGUUAAUAGCGAGGGAAAUUGGUUGCUAGGUAUACAAGAAUUCUUUCCAUCCUUGCAACUUUUCUGUAAAUCUAAAGUUACUCUAAAACUUUUUAAAAAAUCAUUACAUGUGCACAGCAGCAGAAGAGAGAAGACGGAGAGAAGAAUUGCUGAACUUUAUGACAGAACAAUAGAAAUGAGUCAUUCUUUACAGAGAAAAAACUAGACUGAAUAAAAAUGAACAGAACCCCAGAAACUACAAGAAAAUCUCUAACGUUUGUGUAAUUUGAAUCCCAUAAGAAAAGGCUAAAAAAAAAAUUCAAAGAAAUAAUGGCUAAAAUUUUCACAAAUGUGGCAAAGGACAUAAUCCUAGAGAUUCAAGAAGCUGAGUAAAUUCUAUACAGGAUAAACCCAAAGGAAUUCAUGCCAAGAAGCAUAAUUAUGAAACUUCUGACAACUAAAGAUAAAGAAAAAAAUCUGACAAGCAACUAAAGGGAAACAAUAUAUUACUUCUGGGGAAAAAGAAUUUGAAUACAAGUGGAUUUCUUAUUAGAAACCACAGAGAACACAUUUUUCAAGUGCUGAAAGAAAAGAAUUGUUAUCACAACUCUUUAUCCAGCGUAAAUAUCUCUUGGAAAUGAAGGGAAAAUUGAGACAUUCUCAGAUGAAGGGAAACUAAGAGUUUAUUGCCAGCAUACCUACCCCGAAAGAAUGGAAGGAAGGAAGUUCUUGGAACAGAAAUCAUAAAAGGAAUCUUUCAAGCAUCAGGAAAGAAGAAAGAACAAUGCAAAGAGUAAAAAUGCUGGUAGAUACAAUAUGCCUGCCUUCCCUCUUGAGUUUUCUAAUUUUGUUUGAUGGUUGAAGGGAAAAAUUGAACAUUCUCUGAUGUGCUUCUCAAUGUAUAUAGAUGAAAUAGUUAAGAUUAUCAUAUUAUAAACAGGAAGCAGAUAAGGGACUUAGAGUCCCUUCAUCUUUACACUCCACCUCAACCAGCAAAAUAUUGACACUUGUCACAGUGAACUGUGGUAAUAUGUGUAUAAUUUAAUAUAUAGAGUAACCACUAAAAAAACUACAUUAAAUGGUAUACUCAAAAAUAUUACAGAAAAAUAGAUAAGUAAAAAAUGGAAUUCUAAAAAAAAUGUUCAAGAGAGAAGAUCAGGGAAAAAUGAAUAAAAAUUCAAGGGAACAAAAAAAACAAAUAAAAUGGCAGCUUAUCAAAAAUUACGUUAAAUGGUCUAAAUAUACUAAUUAAAAGACAGAUUGAAAGAGUUGGUUUUUAAAAUUCACCUAAAUGUAUGCCAUCUACAAGAAAUUCACUUAAAAAAUAAUAGGUAGAUUGAAAGUAAAAGAACAGAAGAAGGUAUACCAUGGAACAUUAAUCAUAAAAAAGCAGGAUUGGCUAUGUUAAUAUCAGAUAAAACAGACUUCAGAGCACAGAAAAUUAUUGGUAACAGAGUGAUGUUACAUGUCAGUCUGCCAAGAAGACAGCAAUUUUUUUUUUUUUUUUGAGACAGAGUCUCACUCUGUCGUCCAGGCUGGAGUGCAGUGGCACUAUCUCAGCUCACUGCAACCUCCACCUCCUGGGUUCAUGCCAUUCUCCUGCCUCAGCCUCCUGAGUAGCUGGGACUACAGACGCCUGCCACCAUGUCCAGCUAAUUUUUUUUUUGUAUUUUUAGUAGAGAGAGAGUUUCACCAUGUUAGCCAGGAUGGUCUCAAUCUCCAGACCUCGUGAUCCGCCCGUCUCGGCCUCCCAAAGUGCUGGGAUUACAGGUGUGAGCCACGGCGCCCAGCCUAAAGACAGCAAUUUUUAAAUCCUAAAUGUUUCAACAUUCUGAGAGAUACAUCUUAUGCAACUGUAGUACAAUGUCAGUAUCAGGAAGUUGACAUUGGCACAACAAGUGUAUAGUUCUGUGUUAUUUAUCACAUAUAUAGAUUGGUGUAACCACCACUACAGUCAAGUCAACAGAACUAUUCAGUCACCACAAAGAGCUUUGUCCUACCCCUUUAUAUAAAGUCAGCCCAACUCCUUUUACUAUCCCUUAACUCAUGGCAGUCACUAACUUGGUAAGCUAUCAUUUCUUUUUAGACUUUUCAGCCCCUCCCUUUCUCCCUUUUCUCCCCUCCUUCUGAAACUUCUAUGACACAAUUGUUAGAUAUUAUGUUAUAGUCUCACAGGUCCCUGUGGCGUUAGUCUGUUUUCUGUCUGUUGUUCAGAUUGGGUAAUUUCUGCUCUUCUAUAUUAAAAUUCAUGGAUUAUUUCCUCUGUCCUCUUCAUUCUGCUGUUGAACCCAUCCACUGAGUAUUUAGUUAUUUUUCAACUCUAAAAUACCUACUUCAUAUAUCUUCUCUUUCUUUGCUGAGACUUUCUAUUUUUGUUUCAUGUUUCUUAUUGUUUGUUUAAACAUUUAUAUGAUGGCUUAUUUAAAGUCUUUAUCAGAUAUUUUUAACUUCCAUGCCAUCUCAGUGUUGGCAUCUAUUGAUUGUCUUUGCUCAAUCAAGUUGAAGUUGUCUUAGAUCUUGGUAUGACAAGUGAUUUUAGAUUGAACCUAUUUGGAAAUUAUAAGAUCUGUGUCUGAUUUAAAUCUUCUCAUGUAGCAGGCAUUCUCUGACACCACUGUGGCAGGGGAGGUUGGGGGGUGCUGCCUUAUUAUUAAAAGGUGGGCUGAAAGUCCAGGUUUCCUACUCAGCCUCUGUCGGCACCUAGAGGAGGAGGGAUUGUCAUUACUGCUGAAUGGUAGUGGUGGUUCAGCAUCCCCAUUAUGCCUUCACUGAUAACACCCUGCAUGGUAGGAUCUGGAGUGCCUCAUUACUGCUCCCCAUGGGGCUUCUACUGACACUGGGGGGCAGGGGACCUUGUCACUGCCUGGCUUGGAGACAUGUCUCAGCCCCGUCAGCCCUCUCUCACAUGACCCUGGUGGAACAGUAAGGGAGCCUUCUUACAGCCUGGCUACUGCUUUACAAAACCAGAACUGAUCUUCACAUUGGAACAAGGAGAAGAUCCAUGGUUAUUAGAGAAAGAGAAAGGAUUUCUAAGCAGGAACUCCCCAGAAGACUCCCAACCUGAUGAAAUCUCAGAGAAGAGCCCAGAAAAUCAAGGCAAACAUUUGUUGCAAGUUUUAUUCACCAAUAAAUUAUUGACUACAGAGCAAGAAAUUUCAGGAAAACCACAUAAUCGAGACAUAAACAUUUUUCGUGCAAGAAUGAUGCCUUGUAAAUGUGACAUUGCGGGGUCUGCUUGCCAGGGGCUCAGCCUGAUGGCCCCACACUGUCAGUAUUCAAAAGAAAAGGCUCAUGAGCGUAAUGUUUGUGACAAAUGGCUCAUCAGUAUUAAGGAUGGCAGAACUAACACUCAAGAGAAAUCUUUCGCUUAUAGUAAAAUUGUGAAAACCCUCCAUCAUAAGGAGGAAGUUAUUCAACAUCAGACAAUUCAGACUCUGGGGCAAGAUUUUGAAUAUAAUGAAAGUAGAAAAGCUUUUCUUGAAAAGGCUGCCCUUGUUACAUCUAACAGUACCCACCCAAAAGGAAAAUCUUACAAUUUCAAUAAAUUUGGGGAAAACAAAUAUGAUAAAUCAACCUUUAUUAUUCCUCAGAACAUGAAUCCAGAGAAGAGUCACUAUGAGUUUAAUGAUACUGGAAAUUGUUUCUGUAGAAUCACUCACAAAACUCUCACAGGAGGGAAAUCCUUCAGCCAAAAGUCACACAUUAGAGAACAUCAUAGAGUUCAUAUAGGGGUGAAACCCUUUGAAUAUGGAAAAAGUUUCAACCGUAAUUCAACCCUCCCAGUGCAUCAGAGAACUCAUGCAACAGAUAAAUACUCUGAUUAUCACCCAUGUACAGAGACAUUCAGCUACCAGUCAACUUUCAGUGUACAUCAGAAGGUUCACAUAAGGGCAAAACCCUAUGAGUAUAAUGAAUGUGGGAAAUCCUGCUCUAUGAAUUCACACUUGAUUUGGCCUCAGAAAAGUCACACAGGGGAGAAACCCUAUGAAUGUCCUGAGUGCGGGAAAGCCUUCAGUGAGAAGUCACGCCUAAGAAAACAUCAGAGAACUCACACGGGAGAGAAACCAUACAAAUGUGAUGGAUGUGAUAAAGCUUUCAGUGCAAAGUCAGGCCUAAGAAUACACCAGAGAACCCACACAGGGGAGAAACCAUUCGAAUGUCAUGAAUGUGGGAAAUCUUUUAACUAUAAGUCAAUCCUCAUAGUGCAUCAGAGAACUCACACAGGGGAGAAACCUUUUGAAUGUAAUGAAUGCGGGAAAUCUUUCAGCCAUAUGUCAGGCCUAAGGAAUCACCGAAGAACUCACACAGGGGAAAGACCAUAUAAAUGUGAUGAAUGUGGGAAAGCUUUCAAACUGAAGUCAGGCCUGAGGAAACAUCAUAGAACACACACAGGGGAGAAGCCCUACAAAUGUAAUCAGUGUGGAAAAGCUUUCGGUCAGAAAUCACAACUCAGAGGACAUCAUAGAAUUCACACAGGGGAAAAACCCUAUAAAUGUAAUCAUUGUGGGGAAGCUUUCAGUCAGAAAUCAAACCUCAGAGUACAUCACAGAACUCAUACUGGGGAGAAACCCUAUCAAUGUGAGGAGUGUGGAAAAACAUUCAGGCAGAAAUCAAAUCUCAGAGGGCAUCAGAGAACUCACACUGGGGAGAAGCCCUAUGAAUGUAAUGAAUGUGGAAAAGCUUUCAGUGAGAAGUCAGUCCUAAGAAAACAUCAGCGAACUCACACCGGGGAGAAACCAUAUAAUUGUAAUCAGUGUGGGGAAGCUUUCAGUCAGAAAUCCAAUCUCAGAGUACAUCAGAGAACUCACACAGGGGAGAAACCCUAUAAAUGUGAUAAAUGUGGGAGAACUUUCAGUCAAAAAUCAAGCCUUAGAGAACAUCAGAAAGCCCACCCAGGGGAUUAAAUGUAUGCAUAUAAAGAAUACGAAAAAACUCUGAGCUGGAAAUCAAACCUCACAAUACAUAAAUGAACACACAGGAGAGAACUGUUAACAUAGUGAGCACUGGAAUUUCCUCUACAAUUUCAGCCUCCACCAAAUAUCAAAGAAUAGAAGAUAAAUUGUUGAAAUCUAUUUUAUAUGGGCAUUCUUUCAGCCAGAGCCCAGUCUUCUAUGGAUAUACAGAACUCACACAGCAAAGAAACCCUAUAAACAUAAUGAAUAUGGAAAAUACUCUUGCGAACUCACUCCUCAGAAAACUCACGCUGCAGAAAAGCUCUGAGAAAGUAAUAAAAAUGUGAAAACUUUGUGCCAACAAUCAAAACUCAUUCACCAUCAGAGAAAUCACACAAUGACAAAAGCUAGAAUAUAAUAAGUGUGUGAUAAACUUUAAUGAAAAGUCAGUACAGCAGAAAAUACAUUCAAGAUAGAGACCUCAUAGUAUAUUAAAACAAACAAGAAAUGAAGUUAAUGGAUGUGGGAAAUUCUUCUGCCAUGUCAACCCUCAUUUUAACCUACACAGAGGUAAUCCCUAUAUGUCGUAUAAUAACUAUUGAAAUGUUCACUAGUAAUCAUUUUCACUUCUCCCUCAUGCCACACCUGGCCUAAAUUUCUCAACCACUCUCUCAUCUAAACGGGGUCAUAUUGUUACCCUCUAGCUAGUGGAAUAUGGGGUCAGUGACAGGUCUUAAAUACAUCAGUCAAAUUCUCAAUAUUUUCUUCUAUCCCUCAUUAGAAUGGAAUGGAGGAAAACCUUGGGACUCAGGCUCUGAUGAUGGAAAGUACAAGAUGGUAGGAACCCGGGUCAGAGAAGGAUCCUGUGGCAUGGAGUUUUCUCCUCCCUGUACACAGUUGGACUUCUUGCAGUGAGGAAAUAAAUGUGUUCCCUGCUGAACUUCUAAAGGUUUGGGUAUACUUGAUACUGACAGAAACUCAACAACCCUCACAUAAUAAAACUUAGGAGUAUGAUUUUUCAGGACAUCUGAACUCAGUGUAUGUCAGAAAAGUCACAUAGGACAAAUCUCGGACAGCAUCCUGAAUGACCAUGGCUUUUAUCCCCAAAGUCUUCCUCAUCAGACAGGUAAUAUCAUAAGAAAUCUGACAUUUUAACAAAUAUAGGAAAUUCUUCACACACACAGACACACACUCACACAUACACACCCAAAGUCUCAUUAAAUAUAUGAUAAUUUAGUUUUGAAUGUGUAAAAGUUUUCAACAAAUUAUCAUAUUUUAUAUCAGAGCUUGUUACAAGGAGAAAAUCUAUCAAUUUGAGAAAGGUAAGUAAUAGCCUUUAUCUAGAUAUUGCUUUAUCAGAACUGUUGUUUCACAUAUAAUAUCAAAACUUUUAAUGAAAUAUAAGACAUUCACUAUAAUAAAAAGCUUAAAAAGAACAAAAAAUAAACUGCAUAAACUGAAAAGCAGUGUUGCAAAUAUGUGAAUGUUUUGUGAGUUAUUGAUUGUUUAUGUAUGUAUAUAUGCAUGGUACUUACCAGGUAUUUGUUUUAUGUUUCUUAGACCUCAACAUUGCUGUAAAAGAAUUGUGUUCCCCUUGCUUUAUAACUACUUUGACAUCAGCUACAAUUUGCCACAUGAAUAUUAAUAACAAACCUUUUACAGAAAA